GUUCGUACCCGGUCCGGGUCGGCUGGGCUGCCCGCCGCUCCGCGCGCCCGGGCGGUCGCAGGUCGCGCCUGCUUUGGCCCCGGCGGGUUCGGCAUCCGAGCCUGGCAGGGGCCAAUAGGGCCUCUGGAGUGCAGUGGCGUGAUCUCGGCUCACUACAGCGUCUGCCUACCGUGUUCAAGCGAUCCUCCCACCUCAGCCUGUUGAGCAACCGGGACCCCAGGUGCACACUCCACCACGCCCAGCUAAUUUUUUUGUGUUUUGGGUAGAGAGGGGGUCUCACUGUGUUGUCCAAGCUGGUCUCGAACUCCUGAUCUAAAGCGAUCUGCCUGCCUUGGCCUCCCAAAGUGCGAGGACUACAGGCGUGAGCCACCGCGCCUGGCCUGAAGCAGUUUUUCCUUAGACUGUAGUUGGAGGGGGUGAGACCACGUGGAGUGGUUGGCAGACAGGCAGGCACCCUUUGAGGCCAAAAGGGCGCUUGAGACAGAGCCAGCAGGCGAGCGGGCCGCCCAGGUCCCUGGCCCCCUGCUGCCAGUAUGAAGGUCCCACCAAGCCUCUGCUCCAACCAGGGGAACCGUCAUGGUUGGGAACAGCCAAGGUGAGGAAUUCUGUGGGUCACACCCCCUGAAAACCACUGGCCUCCGCCGGGCGCGGUGGCUCACGCUUGUUAUCCCAACACUUUGGGAGGCCCAGGCGGGUGGAUCACGAGGUCAGGAGUUCAAGACCAGCCUGGCCAAGAUGGUGAAACCCCGUCUCUACUAAGAAAAAUACAAAAAUUAGCAGUGGCAGCACCUGUCAUCCAAGCUACUUGGGAGGCUGAGGCGGGAGAAUCACGUGAACCCAGCGGGGGCAGAGGUUGCAAUGAACCAAGAUUGCGCCACUGCACUCCAGCCUGGGCGACAGAUUGAGACUCCUUCUCAAAAAAAAAAAAAAGCCACUGGCCUCUGGCUCCCCCUGGCCCAGCCUGGAGAAGGGUCCCUGACCCCCGUCAGACAAGCAGUGCACCCUGCCUCACCUGACACAGAGCCCUCCCACCACAGGGGAAGUGGGAGCUGGGAGCUCCUGGUACAGGCAAGGCCGAGAGUUGGGUUAGGGAGCAGAGGACGGAGCUGAGUGAGUGUCCAGUGUUAGGUGGGUGGGGGUGUUAGUGGAUGGAGGUGUCUGAAGCCUCGCAGGCCUGCGGUCACACCACAGGCUGGGCCUAGCCGCUUGGAGAGCUUUCUGGAUCUGCACAGGAUCUUGUCCCCCACAGACACACACUGUGGGCCUCAAACCCGGGAGCAGGAGGGGCAGGUUGGAGCAGGUCUACCUGCUUGCCCAGCCCCACCUGCACUGGCCCCAAGGUGUCCCUGAUGGAGCUGAGCUGGACCAGCCACAGGUGCAGGGCUGAGUCUGCAGCAGCCCCCUCCCCAUUCCUCUUCCCCUCCCCCAAGUUAGAACAGCAGUAUGGAGGAGGAAGCUGGAAGCCAGGCUUGGCCCUCACGCUGGCGGCAAGUCUAAUGCGUGUGUGUGCACCUGUGUCCACAGGUGGUGUGCCCCCUAGUGUACCCUUGGGUCCCCACCGUAGUCCAAGGUGUCAUGUCUGUGUGUGGGCAUCGCUGGUUCCCGGCACAGCCAAUCCUGGGAAAGUGCAUGUCCCUCAUGGCAUUCGGAGUCAGGGUGGCCAGCCAGGGCCCCACCAGCAAGCCAUAGCAUCAGCCCAAGGGCAGCAGCCAGCCAGGAGGCAGGAACCGCACCCGAAGUUCCUAGGCGUCCCGAGUCUCCUGUGGGCAAGAUCACCCUUGUACCCUCACUGCUGAGCCCUGGAGUGUGGGUGCCCCCAGGUGGUCUGUUGCUGCUCCGCUACUCCGCAGCAGCCCCCAACCCUGUGUGCCCACCCAGGGUGCCGCCAUCUCCUCCCCUGCAAGAGGCCAGCCUCUGCUCCGCGCCUCUCUAUCCCCAGCAGGUGGGAAAGGGUGCUUCCAGGGUACUGCUAUCUCCCCCGCUCCAAGAGGCCAGCCUCUGCUCCCCGCCUCUCUACCCCUGGCUGGUGGGAAAGGGUGCUCCUCAGGCCCUGUUUAGGGCUGACAUUGGGCCAGGUGACAGGACACCUGGGCAUGAUUGGGCAGCUAUUGGGGAGCCAUGGGCAGAGCACCUGAGGUCUGCAGUCAGCAGCCCAGUCCGGGUGAUGCCUCCUGGGAAGGGGCCCAGACUUGGGGGUAACGGCGUCACUGAUGUGGGUCCCUGGCCCCACUGUGGGGUGUCCAGGGUUGUGCCUAUUGGACCGCCCGCCUCACCAUCCCACGCUACUGAGCCUCCUUCCUCAGCCAUUGUCCAGCUUCGUGUCAAGUCCUGGCGUGGGGCUCACCGCCUGCCCCUUGACCGUGGAGUUCGGACGCGUCUCACAGUGAGUGCCCCAGCAGAGCAGGGUUGGGUGCUGAGCAUCAGCAGCUCUGCCAGAGCAAGUGGCAAUUCCCUGGAACCUGGGGUCUUGCCUUUGUUUGGAGACCGAGAGACUCACAGUGUGGGAGGGUCACAGGACAUGUCAUCAGCAGUGAAAAGGUUUUGUUCCGUUUCCUGCCUUCAGAACUUGCACGUGCUGGAAUCCAAGGAUGGGUGGGAGAGGGGCCGUUCCUGGAGAUGUCUGCCCUUCGGGGCUGGCCCAUGCCACAGGACCUCCCAUCACCCCUGCUGCCUUGGUUGGUGAAUUCGGGGCAUGCUGAGCCUUUCCCUUGCAGCCUUUGCACUUGCUACUCUUCCCUCCGCUUAUCAAACUCCUAACCAUCCCUCGAAGUCCAUGGGCACCAGAAGCACCGCCUCAGAGACUCACAGACUCAGAUGUACAGAUGUCCCUCAGUAUCCAUGCGGAAUUGAUUCCAGGACCCCUGCAGAUGCUCAAGUCCCUGCUAUAAAAUAGUGUAGUGUUUGGCCAGGCAUGGUGGCUCACGCCUGUAAUCCCAGCACUUUGGGAGGCCAAGGCGGGUGGAUCACCUGAGGUCAGGAGUUUGAGACCAGCCUGGCCAACAUGGUGAAACCCCAUCUCUACUAAAAAUACAAAAAUUAGCUGGGCGUGGUGGUGGGAACCUGUAAUCCCAGCUACUCAGUAGGCUGAGGGAGGUGAAUUACUUGAACCCAGGAAGCGGAGGUUGCAGUUAUCCAAGAUUGCGCCACUGCACUCCAGCCUGGGCGACAGAGCAAGACUUGGUCUCAAAAAAAAAAGGGCGGGGGGCUGUGCGCAGUGGCUCACACCUGUAAUCCCAACAGUUUGGGAGGCUGAGGCGGGGGGAUCACGAGGUCAGGAGUUCGAAACCAGCCUGAAACCCCGUCUCUACUAAAAAUACAAAAAAUUAGCCGGGCAUGGUGGCGUGCCUGUAAUCCCAGCUACUUAGGAGGCUGAGGCAGGAGAAUCGCUUAAACCCAGGAGGCGGAGGUUGCAGUGAGCAGAGAUCAUGCCAUUGCACUCUAGCCUGGGCGACAGAGCAAGACUCCAUCUCAAAAAAAAAAAAAUGGUGUAGUGUUUGCAUAUAACCUACACGUGUCCUUCUGUGUACUUUAACUCAUUUCUAGAUUACUUAUAAUACCUAAUACAAUGUAACUGCUGUGGGAAGAGUUGCUAUAUUGUGUUGUUUAGGAAAUAACAAGAAAAAAAAAAGCACAACCA